GUCAGCAGGCAACAUGGCCGAGAGGCCGGGGCCUCCGGGCGGCGCCGUGUCCGCGACCGCGUACCCUGACACCCCCGCGGAAUUCCCUCCGCACCUCCAGGCGGGUGCGAUGCGGCGCCGCUUUUGGGGCGUAUUCAACUGUCUGUGCGCCGGCGCGUUCGGGGCCCUGGCCGCCGCCUCCGCCAAGCUGGCCUUCGGCAGCGAGGUGAGCAUGGGUUUAUGCGUCUUAGGCAUUAUUGUGAUGGCGAGCACCAAUUCUCUGAUGUGGACCUUCUUUAGCCGGGGCCUCAGUUUCUCCAUGUCUUCAGCCAUUGCAUCUGUCACAGUGACUUUUUCAAAUAUCCUCAGCUCGGCCUUCCUGGGCUAUGUGCUGUAUGGAGAGUGCCAGGAGGUCUUGUGGUGGGGAGGAGUGUUCCUUAUUCUCUGCGGACUCACCCUAAUCCACAGGAAGCUCCCACCCACCUGGAAGCCCCUUCCACACAAGCAGCAGUAGCACCACUUGGCUAGACGGACCAGCUGGAAAGAUCAUGAUGGUGGCCCAGCCUUGGGAUGUCAUGUGGGACUGUAUCCUAGGGCGAUCCAGUUGUGCAGCCUUCUGACCAUCAGCCAAGGGAAGCAGGCCUCUGAUGGAGCAGGCUCUGGCUCUGUAAGGAGAGGUGCAGCUGCAGCAGUGUUCUACCGGAAGUGUUUUGAUCAUCUGUACAGUGCUUUGGAUUCUUCCUCCCAGGCCUACCCCAGUGAGCCUUCGCAGAUGCUGGAGAUCCUGGGGUUGGUCUGCUUUGUGUAUGGUACUUGAAACCACGCUGUAAUUAUUGUCCUGUUGCCAAACAAAAGCCAGUCAUGUAACUCUAGAAGCAGUGACUGGUGGGGCUUUCUGACAGUUCCAUGCUGAUGUAUCAGGCCAUCUGUGUCAUGCUUAUGUAUUAUGGCAAGAAGAGGAAAACUGGAUUAAUAAAUACGUUUUUUGUAAGUUAAAA